GUGGUUGACUAGUGCCUCGCAGCCUCAGCAUGGGGGAACAUGGCCUGGAGCUGGCUUCCAUGAUCCCCGCCCUGCGGGAGCUGGGCAGUGCCACACCAGAGGAAUAUAAUACAGUUGUACAGAAGCCAAGACAAAUUCUGUGUCAAUUCAUUGACCGGAUACUUACAGAUGUAAAUGUUGUUGCUGUAGAACUUGUAAAGAAAACUGACUCUCAGCCAACCUCCGUGAUGUUGCUUGAUUUCAUCCAGCAUAUCAUGAAAUCCUCCCCACUUAUGUUUGUAAAUGUGAGUGGAAGCCAUGAGGCCAAAGGCAGUUGUAUUGAAUUCAGUAAUUGGAUCAUAACGAGACUUCUGCGGAUUGCAGCAACUCCCUCCUGUCAUUUGUUACACAAGAAAAUCUGUGAAGUCAUCUGUUCAUUAUUAUUUCUUUUUAAAAGCAAGAGUCCUGCUAUUUUUGGGGUACUCACAAAAGAAUUAUUACAACUUUUUGAAGACUUGGUUUACCUCCAUAGAAGAAAUGUGAUGGGUCAUGCUGUGGAAUGGCCAGUGGUCAUGAGCCGAUUUUUAAGUCAAUUAGAUGAACACAUGGGAUAUUUACAAUCAGCUCCUUUGCAGUUGAUGAGUAUGCAAAAUUUAGAAUUUAUUGAAGUCACUUUAUUAAUGGUUCUUACUCGUAUUAUUGCAAUUGUGUUUUUUAGAAGGCAAGAACUCUUACUUUGGCAGAUAGGUUGUGUUCUGCUAGAGUAUGGUAGUCCAAAAAUUAAAUCCCUAGCAAUUAGCUUUUUAACAGAACUUUUUCAGCUUGGAGGACUACCAGCACAACCAGCUAGCACUUUUUUCAGCUCAUUUUUGGAAUUAUUAAAACACCUUGUAGAAAUGGAUACUGACCAAUUGAAACUCUAUGAAGAGCCAUUAUCAAAGCUGAUAAAGACACUAUUUCCCUUUGAAGCAGAAGCUUAUAGAAAUAUUGAACCUGUCUAUUUAAAUAUGCUGCUGGAAAAACUCUGUGUCAUGUUUGAAGACGGUGUGCUCAUGCGGCUUAAGUCUGAUUUGCUAAAAGCAGCUUUGUGCCAUUUACUGCAGUAUUUCCUUAAAUUUGUGCCAGCUGGGUAUGAAUCUGCUUUACAAGUCAGGAAGGUCUAUGUGAGAAAUAUUUGUAAAGCUCUUUUGGAUGUGCUUGGAAUUGAGGUAGAUGCAGAGUACUUGUUGGGCCCACUUUAUGCAGCUUUGAAAAUGGAAAGUAUGGAAAUCAUUGAGGAGAUUCAAUGCCAAACUCAACAGGAAAACCUCAGCAGUAAUAGUGAUGGAAUAUCACCCAAAAGGCGUCGUCUCAGCUCGUCUCUAAACCCUUCUAAAAGAGCACCAAAACAGACUGAGGAAAUUAAACAUGUGGACAUGAACCAAAAGAGCAUAUUAUGGAGUGCACUGAAACAGAAAGCUGAAUCCCUUCAGAUUUCCCUUGAAUACAGUGGCCUAAAGAAUCCUGUUAUUGAGAUGUUAGAAGGAAUUGCUGUUGUCUUACAACUGACUGCUCUGUGUACUGUUCAUUGUUCUCAUCAAAACAUGAACUGCCGUACUUUCAAGGACUGUCAACAUAAAUCCAAGAAGAAACCUUCUGUAGUGAUAACUUGGAUGUCAUUGGAUUUUUACACAAAAGUGCUUAAGAGCUGUAGAAGUUUGUUAGAAUCUGUUCAGAAACUGGACCUGGAGGCAACCAUUGAUAAGGUGGUGAAAAUUUAUGAUGCUUUGAUUUAUAUGCAAGUAAACAGUUCAUUUGAAGAUCAUAUCCUGGAAGAUUUAUGUGGUAUGCUCUCACUUCCAUGGAUUUAUUCCCAUUCUGAUGAUGGCUGUUUAAAGUUGACCACAUUUGCCGCUAAUCUUCUAACAUUAAGCUGUAGGAUUUCAGAUAGCUAUUCACCACAGGCACAAUCACGAUGUGUGUUUCUUCUGACUCUGUUUCCAAGAAGAAUAUUCCUUGAGUGGAGAACAGCAGUUUACAACUGGGCCCUGCAGAGCUCCCAUGAAGUAAUCCGGGCUAGUUGUGUUAGUGGAUUUUUUAUCUUAUUGCAGCAGCAGAAUUCUUGUAACAGAGUUCCCAAGAUUCUUAUAGAUAAAGUCAAAGAUGAUUCUGACAUUGUCAAGAAAGAAUUUGCUUCUAUACUUGGUCAACUUGUCUGUACUCUUCACGGCAUGUUUUAUCUGACAAGUUCUUUAACAGAACCUUUCUCUGAACACGGACAUGUGGACCUCUUCUGUAGGAACUUGAAAGCCACUUCUCAACAUGAAUGUUCAUCUUCUCAACUAAAAGCUUCUGUCUGCAAGCCAUUCCUUUUCCUACUGAAAAAAAAAAUACCUAGUCCAGUAAAACUUGCUUUCAUAGAUAAUCUACAUCAUCUUUGUAAGCAUCUUGAUUUUAGAGAAGAUGAAACAGAUGUAAAAGCAGUUCUUGGAACUUUAUUAAAUUUAAUGGAAGAUCCAGACAAAGAUGUUAGAGUGGCUUUUAGUGGAAAUAUCAAGCACAUAUUGGAAUCCUUGGACUCUGAAGAUGGAUUUAUAAAGGAGCUUUUUGUCUUAAGAAUGAAGGAAGCAUAUACACAUGCCCAAAUAUCAAGAAAUAAUGAGCUGAAGGAUACCUUGAUUCUUACAACAGGGGAUAUUGGAAGGGCCGCAAAAGGAGAUUUGGUACCAUUUGCACUCUUACACUUAUUGCAUUGUUUGUUAUCCAAGUCAGCAUCUGUCUCUGGAGCAGCAUACACAGAAAUUAGAGCUCUGGUUGCAGCUAAAAGUGUUAAACUGCAAAGUUUUUUCAGCCAGUAUAAGAAACCCAUCUGUCAGUUUUUGGUAGAAUCCCUUCACUCUAGUCAGAUGACAGCACUUCCGAAUACUCCAUGCCAGAAUGCUGACGUGCGAAAACAAGAUGUGGCUCACCAGAGAGAAAUGGCUUUAAAUACGUUGUCUGAAAUUGCCAACGUUUUCGACUUUCCUGAUCUUAAUCGUUUUCUUACUAGGACAUUACAAGUUCUACUACCUGAUCUUGCUGCCAAAGCAAGCCCUGCAGCUUCUGCUCUCAUUCGAACUUUAGGAAAACAAUUAAAUGUCAAUCGUAGAGAGAUUUUAAUAAACAACUUCAAAUAUAUUUUUUCUCAUUUGGUCUGUUCUUGUUCCAAAGAUGAAUUAGAACGUGCCCUUCAUUAUCUGAAGAAUGAAACAGAAAUUGAACUGGGGAGCCUGUUGAGACAAGAUUUCCAAGGAUUGCAUAAUGAAUUAUUGCUGCGUAUUGGAGAACACUAUCAACAGGUUUUUAAUGGUUUGUCAAUACUUGCCUCAUUUGCAUCCAGUGAUGAUCCAUAUCAGGGCCCGAGAGAUAUCAUAUCACCUGAACUGAUGGCUGAUUAUUUACAACCCAAAUUGUUGGGCAUUUUGGCUUUUUUUAACAUGCAGUUACUGAGCUCUAGUGUUGGCAUUGAAGAUAAGAAAAUGGCCUUGAACAGUUUGAUGUCUUUGAUGAAGUUAAUGGGACCCAAACAUGUCAGUUCUGUGAGGGUGAAGAUGAUGACCACACUGAGAACUGGCCUUCGAUUCAAGGAUGAUUUUCCUGAAUUGUGUUGCAGAGCUUGGGACUGCUUUGUUCGCUGCCUGGAUCAUGCUUGUCUGGGCUCCCUUCUCAGUCAUGUAAUAGUAGCUUUGUUACCUCUUAUACACAUCCAGCCUAAAGAAACUGCAGCUAUCUUCCACUACCUCAUAAUUGAAAACAGGGAUGCUGUGCAAGAUUUUCUUCAUGAAAUAUAUUUUUUACCUGAUCAUCCAGAAUUAAAAAAGAUAAAAGCCGUUCUCCAGGAAUACAGAAAGGAGACCUCUGAGAGCACUGAUCUUCAGACAACUCUUCAGCUCUCUAUGAAGGCCAUUCAACAUGAAAAUGUCGAUGUUCGUAUUCAUGCUCUUACAAGCUUGAAGGAAACCUUGUAUAAAAAUCAGGAAAAACUGAUAAAGUAUGCAACAGACAGUGAAACAGUAGAACCUAUUAUCUCACAGUUGGUGACAGUGCUUUUGAAAGGUUGCCAAGAUGCAAACUCUCAAGCUCGGUUGCUCUGUGGGGAAUGUUUAGGGGAAUUGGGGGCGAUAGAUCCAGGUCGAUUAGAUUUCUCAACAACUGAAACUCAAGGAAAAGAUUUUACAUUUGUGAUUGAGACUGGAGUAGAAGAUUCAAGCUUUGCCUAUGGAUUAUUGAUGGAGCUAACAAGAGCUUACCUUGCGUAUGCUGAUAAUAGCCGAGCUCAAGAUUCAGCUGCCUAUGCCAUUCAGGAGUUGCUUUCUAUUUAUGACUGUAGAGAGAUGGAGACCAACGGCCCAGGUCACCAAUUGUGGAGGAGAUUUCCUGAGCAUGUUCGGGAAAUACUAGAACCUCAUCUAAAUACCAGAUACAAGAGUUCUCAGAAGUCAACCGAUUGGUCUGGAGUAAAGAAGCCAAUUUACUUAAGUAAAUUGGGUAGUAACUUUGCAGAAUGGUCAGCAUCUUGGGCAGGUUAUCUUAUUACAAAGGUUCGACAUGAUCUUGCCAGUAAAAUUUUCACCUGCUGUAGCAUUAUGAUGAAGCAUGAUUUCAAAGUGACCAUCUAUCUUCUUCCACAUAUUCUGGUGUAUGUCUUACUGGGUUGUAAUCAAGAAGAUCAGCAGGAGGUUUAUGCAGAAAUUAUGGCAGUUCUAAAGCAUGACGAUCAGCAUACCAUAAAUACCCAAGACAUUGCAUCUGAUCUGUGUCAACUCAGUACACAGACUGUGUUCUCCAUGCUUGACCAUCUCACACAGUGGGCAAGGCACAAAUUUCAGGCACUGAAAGCUGAGAAAUGUCCACACAGCAAAUCAAACAGAAAUAAGGUAGACUCAAUGGUAUCUACUGUGGAUUAUGAAGACUAUCAGAGUGUAACCCGUUUUCUAGACCUCAUACCCCAGGAUACUCUGGCAGUAGCUUCCUUUCGCUCCAAAGCAUACACACGAGCUGUAAUGCACUUUGAAUCAUUUAUUACAGAAAAGAAGCAAAAUAUUCAGGAACAUCUUGGAUUUUUACAGAAAUUGUAUGCUGCUAUGCAUGAACCUGAUGGAGUGGCCGGAGUCAGUGCAAUUAGAAAGGCAGAACCAUCUCUAAAAGAACAGAUCCUUGAACAUGAAAGCCUUGGCUUGCUGAGGGAUGCCACUGCUUGUUAUGACAGGGCUAUUCAGCUAGAACCAGACCAGAUCAUUCAUUAUCAUGGUGUAGUAAAGUCCAUGUUAGGUCUUGGUCAGCUGUCUACUGUUAUCACUCAGGUGAAUGGAGUGCAUGCUAACAGGUCCGAGUGGACAGAUGAAUUAAACACGUACAGAGUGGAAGCAGCUUGGAAAUUGUCACAGUGGGAUUUGGUGGAAAACUAUUUGGCAGCAGAUGGAAAAUCUACAACAUGGAGUGUCAGACUGGGACAGCUAUUAUUAUCAGCCAAAAAAAGAGAUAUCACAGCUUUUUAUGACUCACUGAAACUAGUGAGAGCAGAACAAAUUGUACCUCUUUCAGCUGCAAGCUUUGAAAGAGGCUCCUACCAACGAGGAUAUGAAUAUAUUGUGAGAUUGCACAUGUUAUGUGAGUUGGAGCAUAGCAUCAAACCACUUUUCCAGCAUUCUCCAGGUGACAGUUCUCAAGAAGAUUCUCUAAACUGGGUAGCUCGACUAGAAAUGACCCAGAAUUCCUACAGAGCCAAGGAGCCUAUCCUGGCUCUCCGGAGGGCUUUACUAAGCCUCAACAAAAGACCAGAUUACAAUGAAAUGGUUGGAGAAUGCUGGCUGCAGAGUGCCAGGGUAGCUAGAAAGGCUGGUCACCACCAGACAGCCUACAAUGCUCUCCUUAAUGCAGGGGAAUCACGACUCGCUGAACUGUACGUGGAAAGGGCAAAGUGGCUCUGGUCCAAGGGUGAUGUUCACCAGGCACUAAUUGUUCUUCAAAAAGGUGUUGAAUUAUGUUUUCCUGAAAAUGAAACCCCACCUGAGGGUAAGAACAUGUUAAUCCAUGGUCGAGCUAUGCUACUAGUGGGCCGAUUUAUGGAAGAAACAGCUAACUUUGAAAGCAAUGCAAUUAUGAAAAAAUAUAAGGAUGUGACCGCGUGCCUGCCAGAAUGGGAGGAUGGGCAUUUUUACCUUGCCAAGUACUAUGACAAAUUGAUGCCCAUGGUCACAGACAACAAAAUGGAAAAGCAAGGUGAUCUCAUCCGGUAUAUAGUUCUUCAUUUUGGCAGAUCUCUACAAUAUGGAAAUCAGUUCAUAUAUCAGUCAAUGCCACGAAUGUUAACUCUAUGGCUUGAUUAUGGUACAAAGGCAUAUGAAUGGGAAAAAGCUGGCCGCUCCGAUCGUGUACAAAUGAGGAAUGAUUUGGGUAAAAUAAACAAGGUUAUCACAGAGCAUACAAACUAUUUAGCUCCAUAUCAAUUUUUGACUGCUUUUUCACAAUUGAUCUCUCGAAUUUGUCAUUCUCACGAUGAAGUUUUUGUUGUCUUGAUGGAAAUAAUAGCCAAAGUAUUUCUAGCCUAUCCUCAACAAGCAAUGUGGAUGAUGACAGCUGUGUCAAAGUCAUCUUAUCCCAUGCGUGUGAACAGAUGCAAGGAAAUCCUCAAUAAAGCUAUUCAUAUGAAAAAAUCCUUAGAGAAGUUUGUUGGAGAUGCAACUCGCCUAACAGAUAAGCUUCUAGAAUUGUGCAAUAAACCGGUUGAUGGAAGUAGUUCCACAUUAAGCAUGAGCACUCAUUUUAAAAUGCUUAAAAAGCUGGUAGAAGAAGCAACAUUUAGUGAAAUCCUCAUUCCUCUACAAUCAGUCAUGAUACCUACACUUCCAUCAAUUCUGGGUACCCAUGCUAACCAUGCUAGCCAUGAACCAUUUCCUGGACAUUGGGCCUAUAUUGCAGGGUUUGAUGAUAUGGUGGAAAUUCUUGCUUCUCUUCAGAAACCAAAGAAGAUUUCUUUAAAAGGCUCAGAUGGAAAGUUCUACAUCAUGAUGUGUAAGCCAAAAGAUGACCUGAGAAAGGAUUGUAGACUAAUGGAAUUCAAUUCCUUGAUUAAUAAGUGCUUAAGAAAAGAUGCAGAGUCUCGUAGAAGAGAACUUCAUAUUCGAACAUAUGCAGUUAUUCCACUAAAUGAUGAAUGUGGGAUUAUUGAAUGGGUGAACAACACUGCUGGUUUGAGACCUAUUCUGACCAAACUAUAUAAAGAAAAGGGAGUGUAUAUGACAGGAAAAGAACUUCGCCAGUGUAUGCUACCAAAGUCAGCAGCUUUAUCUGAAAAACUCAAAGUAUUCCGAGAAUUUCUCCUGCCCAGGCAUCCUCCUAUUUUUCAUGAGUGGUUUCUGAGAACAUUCCCUGAUCCUACAUCAUGGUACAGUAGUAGAUCAGCUUACUGCCGUUCCACUGCAGUAAUGUCAAUGGUUGGUUAUAUUCUGGGGCUUGGAGACCGUCAUGGUGAAAAUAUUCUCUUUGAUUCUUUGACUGGUGAAUGCGUACAUGUAGAUUUCAAUUGUCUUUUCAAUAAGGGAGAAACCUUUGAAGUUCCAGAAAUUGUGCCAUUUCGCCUGACUCAUAAUAUGGUUAAUGGAAUGGGUCCUAUGGGAACAGAGGGUCUUUUUCGAAGAGCAUGUGAAGUUACAAUGAGGCUGAUGCGUGAUCAGCGAGAGCCUUUAAUGAGUGUCUUAAAGACUUUUCUACAUGAUCCUCUUGUGGAAUGGAGUAAACCAGUGAAAGGGCAUUCCAAAGCGCCACUGAAUGAAACUGGAGAAGUUGUCAAUGAAAAGGUUAGUAGAAGGUAUAGCUUGAUAUGGGCUGUAGUCCUCAUCUCUACAAAUGAACUUGAUAUGCAGCUAUAGUUCUCAUCUCUAUGCAUGAGAACUGCUUGGAAAUACUGUUAGUGACUAUUGAUUACUCUGAAAUCUAGUUCUCUAGUAUCACAAUGCCAUAAGUUUUCUUUAUUGUCAGUAAUGUUAACAGUAUUCGCAUUUGUAUAAUAAAAGUUCAUGGCACACUUGUUUAACCAUAGACAAUUCACAGUUAUGAGAUACAGUAGGAAAAACUAUAGUACAAAUUGCCUGAACUUACAGAACAACAGGUCUGAGCUUUAAUAUCAUGAUACCAGUAUGUCACAAGCUAUGUUAACAAAUGCAGCAAUUCACUUCUUACUUAGUUGAAGCUGCAAAGUUUGCAGAUAGUUUUGUUGUUGUUGUUGUGGUGGUGGUGGUGGUUGUUGUUUUUGAGACAGAGUCUCGCUCUGUCAUCCAGGCUGGAGUACAGUGGCACGAUCUUGGCUCACGGCAACCUCUGCCUCCUGGGUUCAAGCAGUUCUCCUGCCUUAGCCUCCCAAGUAGCUGGGAUUAUAAGCGUGCACCACCACAGCUGGCUAAUUAUUAUAUUUUUAGUAGAGAUGGGUUUCACCAUGUUGGCCAGGCUGGUCUUGAACCCCUGGCUUCAAGUGAUCCACCCACCUCAGCAUCCCAAAAUGCAGGGAUUAUAGGCAUAAGCCACUGUGCCUAGCUCAGAUAGUUGUUUUUAAUAAGUUAGAAUAGAUUGAGGAUUCGUUUUUUUUGGUGGGGGGCACUCUUACAUCUUUAAUAAGUCUUGUACAGGCUUACUAAAUACAAUGAAUUAUACCAACUAUAUGCUAAUAAAGAUUAAAAAUUUACAUUCCAGUUAACUACCUAAAGAGUUUAAGUCCACUUUCAUCCUACUGAUAUAGCUCGAGGAAGGCUAGACCUGUACGCCCCCAUCCUUCAUGUCAUCCUUAACCCUUUGUCUUGAGAAAGAAGGUUUAGCUGCUUCUUUAGUUCUUCUAAAAGAACUAAAAGAAAAAUUUCUUUUUCUUGCUCUAUUAUCUUCAUCUGUAGGGUGAGAUUAAUAUUUCCAGAAUUGUGGAAAAAUUCACUCUGUAGCAGUUGAAGAGCAGAUGGUCUCUGGGACAUGUUCCUUUUCGUUAAGUGAUAGAUAUACUUGGCUUGUACUGGAUACCUUUUACUGAGGGAUUCCAAUAUCUGACCAGUUCUUGAACCUGUUAAAACUUCUGCUCGCUCCAUUUCUGUUCUAAACAGCUGAAAGAGCUCUAGCAGGAUCACACUCAAGCUAUAUACAUAUCUAACUGGACAAAGCCAGCCCUGGUCUCUACAAAUAGUUUUUGUUUUUUUUUAAUUAGCUGGGCUCAGUGGCACACUCCUGUAGUCCCAGCUACUUGGGAGGCUGAGGUGGGAGGAUCACUUGACCCCAGGAGUUGGAGGCUGCUGUGAGCUAUGAUGACACCACUGCACUCCAGCCUGGGCAACAGAGUGAGACCCUUGGCAUCAUACUCAGAUCCUUCCAACUGCUGGGAUGAAGCAUACAGACAAGUGCCCACUCUGGAUAUAGGUGUUGGUGUUCUCUUUCUGUUUCUAUGGGUCCAGUCUGUGUUCUUUUGUAAGAUGUCUGGGCAAGCCAGACCAAAGUCUCCUAUUUUUACUUGCUGAUCAGGGCCAUGAAGAAAAAUAUUUCUAGGCUUCAGAUCUCUGUUUACAAUACCCAUGUUAUGUAUGUAAAACACACCUUCCACUAAAUCUUGAAAAUUUUUUGUUGCAACACUGGCCAUAAGGACAGGCAAACUUGCCCACACACUCUUGGCCCUGUUUGUUUCUCUCAGCUAGCCAGUCCCACAGCUGGAGCUUGCACACCUGCAUCUGGAUGUGCAGCAUCAGGUGGUACUGCACCUCGAUCCCCAACAAGUUGAAGUUUUCUUUGGAAGAUUCCUCAGUGGAUGUGAAAUUCUCCUCUAGGAGGGAAUUACACCUGAGCAGCAGGGGCUGUUUCACAAUUGACCAGGUAGACAAACCAGCCAGGCCAUUUUCCUGGAGCUCCAGGGAUGAUUCAUAUUCACUGGUGUCUCUUAAGACGGAAUUGAUGGUGUAGUUCACAGCUUGUUGUUCUGAUUUUGAGUGUCAGAUUCUGCAAAGGGUUUUUCUUUUCUGAGGUGAGCUCCGCGAAGAUAAUGGGUGAGCUGCUAUUUUCACCAUUUUUAACACCGUAUUGGUAUCUGUCUGCUUGGUCGGAGAACACUUCCAGAAAUGGCAACUGAACGGAAGCUCUGUCUGCUUGUGGUUGGACCACUUGAACAUGUUCUGUCCACGCAGUGUGAUAACGAAUGAUAUUAGGGUGCUGAAGACCUGCCAGCACCUUCAUUCCCCGUAGUUCUUUCAUGUAAUGUGUUUUUGUUGCACCCUUAAUCAGGAUUUUUUAAAUUGCAUAAUACUGACCAUCUAAUUUAUUCCUGACCUUGUAUACUCUUCCAUAUCCACCUUUUCCUAAGAUGGCAAGUUCUUCAAAUUCAUUUAAGUAACGUGAAGUUUGUGC